GGCGGCUGAGAGGCAGCGAACUCAUCUUUGCCAGUACAGGAGCUUGUGCCGUGGCCCACAGCCCACAGCCCACAGCCAUGGGCUGGGACCUGACGGUGAAGAUGCUGGCGGGCAACGAAUUCCAGGUGUCCCUGAGCAGCUCCAUGUCGGUGUCAGAGCUGAAGGCGCAGAUCACCCAGAAGAUCGGCGUGCACGCCUUCCAGCAGCGUCUGGCUGUCCACCCGAGCGGUGUGGCGCUGCAGGACAGGGUCCCCCUUGCCAGCCAGGGCCUGGGCCCCGGCAGCACGGUCCUGCUGGUGGUGGACAAAUGCGACGAACCUCUGAGCAUCCUGGUGAGGAAUAACAAGGGCCGCAGCAGCACCUACGAGGUACGGCUGACGCAGACCGUGGCCCACCUGAAGCAGCAAGUGAGCGGGCUGGAGGGUGUGCAGGACGACCUGUUCUGGCUGACCUUCGAGGGGAAGCCCCUGGAGGACCAGCUCCCGCUGGGGGAGUACGGCCUCAAGCCCCUGAGCACCGUGUUCAUGAAUCUGCGCCUGCGGGGAGGCGGCACAGAGCCUGGCGGGCGGAGCUAAGGGCCUCCACCAGCAUCCGAGCAGGAUCAAGGGCCGGAAAUAAAGGCUGUUGUAAAGAGAAA